CUUCUACGUCGCUGACUCGUGACCUGACCGGUAUUUUUUUCCUAAACUGGGAUCUUGGGUAGGAGGAAGAAAAGAUAAGGAGUUCCUCUAUCUGAAAUUAGUCGGGCUGUUUUGAGGAGUACUGGUUAGAUACCUUCCGAUACUCCUCCAAAGAACUCUCGGAUUCAAGUAAACAAACAUCCAUUAAUACAAGUUAAGUAUGUUCCAGGCGCUGUGUGUUCCAGGUACUGUUAACAAAAGCGGGUUACUAGUUAAGACUUCCUUCAUGCCCUGGCGCCUCUGCUCAGCCAGUUCCCUUCGCCUAGGAGGACCUCUCUACACCACCCCGCUAUAUUCCCUCCCCGGAAUUCCUUCCCAACCUUCAAGGACCAUCUGCCCCAACUAGUGGCGAACAUCGAGGCUGUCGUGACUGUGUAGAUACUUAUUUGACCUGCUCCCUUGGCAAACACUUGAAACGCAAUACAUGUUUGUGGAACUGAACAUAGCCUGUGCAUGCAGCAAGGCUUCUUUCCCUGGAAUCGCCUGCCCUUCCUCCAACACAGCGACCAGCCGGUCAGAAUCCCAACCCCUCGACUCCGGAAAUGAUCUGAGAGACGGAACUUCCGAACGUCGCAAUCAGAUUUGGGCGGGCUAGGAGGGUUUGGGUCUUCAGGUCACAUCUGGACGGAGAGACCUCCGGGGCCUCCGUUGGUCGGUCCUUCCGCUCCGGAUACCGUUCCGGAUGUCAGGUAGUUCAGGUCCCGCCCCGACGCCGGCCGUGACGAAGGCACGCCGGGGUGACCUCACCCUCCAACAUGGCGGCGGCGGUAGAUUAGGGCCGCGGGUCGGAGCACUCACCGCCGCUGGGGGACCCUGUCGGAAGCAACUGCCGCCGCCGCCUCUUUCAUCUCUUCUGGGGCAGGGGCCAGGGCCAGGGGUUCAACUAGAUAUAGCUUCACAAUCUCUGGAUCAAGAAAUUUUAUUAAAAGUUAAAACUGAAAUUGAAGAAGAGCUAAAAUCUCUGGACAAAGAAAUUUCUGAAGCCUUCACCAGCACAGGCUUUGACCGUCACACUUCUCCAGUGUUCAGCCCUGCCAAUCCAGAAAGCUCAAUGGAAGACUGCUUGGCCCAUCUUGGAGAAAAAGUGUCCCAGGAACUGAAAGAGCCUCUCCAUAAAGCAUUGCAAAUGCUCCUGAGCCAGCCAGUGACAUAUCAGGCAUUUCGGGAAUGUACACUGGAGACCACAGUUCAUGCCAGCGGCUGGAAUAAGAUUUUGGUGCCUCUGGUUUUGCUACGACAAAUGCUUUUGGAAUUGACAAGACGUGGUCAAGAACCUUUGAGCGCACUGCUGCAGUUUGGCGUGACAUACCUGGAGGACUAUUCGGCAGAGUACAUCAUUCAGCAAGGUGGCUGGGGCACUGUGUUUAGUCUUGAGUCAGAGGAGGAGGAAUACCCUGGAAUCACUGCAGAAGAUAGCAAUGACAUUUACAUCCUGCCCAGCGACAACUCUGGACAAGUCAGUCCCCCAGAGUCUCCAACUGUGACCACUUCCUGGCAGUCUGAGAGCUUACCUGUGUCACUGUCAGCUAGCCAGAGUUGGCACACAGAAAGCCUGCCAGUGUCACUAGGCCCUGAGUCCUGGCAGCAGAUUGCAAUGGAUCCUGAAGAAGUGAAAAGCUUAGACAGCAACGGAGCUGGAGAGAAGAGUGAGAACAACUCCUCUAAUUCUGACAUUGUGCACGUGGAGAAAGAAGAGGUGCCCGAGGGCAUGGAAGAGGCUGCUGUGGCUUCUGUGGUCUUGCCAGCGCGGGAGCUGCAAGAGGCACUUCCUGAAGCCCCAGCUCCCUUGCUUCCACAUAUCACUGCCACCUCCCUGCUGGGGACAAGGGAACCUGACACAGAAGUGAUCACAGUUGAGAAAUCCAGCCCUGCUACAUCUCUGUUUGUAGAACUUGAUGAAGAAGAGGUGAAAGCAGCAACAACUGAACCUACUGAAGUGGAGGAGGUGGUCCCCGCACUGGAACCCACAGAAACGCUGCUGAGUGAGAAGGAGAUAAACGCAAGGGAAGAGAGCCUUGUGGAAGAGCUGUCCCCUGCCAGCGAGAAGAAGCCCGUGCCGCCGUCUGAGGGCAAGUCUAGACUGUCCCCCGCCGGUGAGAUGAAGCCCAUGCCGCUGUCUGAGGGCAAGUCUAUACUGCUGUUUGGAGGGGCUGCUGCUGUUGCCAUCCUGGCAGUGGCCAUCGGGGUAGCCCUGGCUCUGAGAAAGAAAUAGGAGGCUUUUCAGAAGAGAAAGACAGAAGGAUGUAAGGUUGGAGUUGUAUUGGCUGGAAUUUGAACCUCCAGCAGCUGUCUGGACAUUUGUGGAACACUCUGGGAUAAUUGGGGACUUCUGCUCAACAUGGCAGUGGCAUGUUAGGCAUGUUAGGGCUUGAGGUGGGGCAUUCACAUUCAUCUGACUGUAAAUCCCAAGGGCCUCCGCUCAUGCUAAAUUGAGAAUCUUAGGGGUAAAGCACCCCCUCCAGGACCGGGUUUCUCAGCCUUGGCACUAGUGCUGUUCUGACCAUUCUCUGUGUUGGGGCUGUCCUGUGUGUGGUGGGCUCCACCCACUAGAUGCCAGUGGCACCCCCUCCCAGAGAUGACAAACGAAAAUGUCUCUAGACAUUGCCAAAUGUCCCGUGUGAACAUCCCCUAUUGAGACCCACUGCUUUAGCGAGAGAGGGUUUACUUAGGAAGAAUUGGGAUAGAAAUUCCCAGCUGAGAGAACUUAGCUGUGGGCUCCUCAGCUACUGACUUCUUAGCUCUUAAUCCCCUUAGAAUUUCAUCUUUCUCGAUGAGCAGGCUCUGCACCCACUCUUUUUUUGCCCCCCGCCCUCAUCCUGGAGUGUGAGGGUGCUCGCCCGUACUCUCAGCUGCCUCUCAGGGACUGCACUGUUCCUCUUCACCCCCAGGUUCCUGCUAAGAUCCCACGGGCGAGGGCUUGCUCUGGACUCAGUCUGUCAAGUCCCCGAAGCUUCCUGCAGCUCCACCUUGUAAAAAUGCUGCCUUUGGGAAUCUUCGAAAUAUGUACACAGAGAAAAUCACAUGAAGGAGACCUGGGGUCCCCACUUGUGAGUGCAACUGCAAGUAACUCUGGCUAGAGAGACACAUGUGUCUUGUGUCAAGGCAGGAGGAUAACCUGGAUGACCUUCUGAGGUCUCUUCAGCCCUUUUCGCUAGUGGUCACCCACCACCAUGGUUACUUGCCAGCAACAUCUCUAUUGCUGGAUGGUCCCUGUCUAUAACCUUGGGCUAGUAUAUUUUUUCCAAUAUGGGACCUUAGUCUUACUACUGAUGAGUUCUAUGGGUCUCUUGCUAGGGGGUAAGGAUUUUUAUUCUUGGGCUUAUAGAGCCAGUUAGAUCAUAAUUCUUAUGAAAUAGAGAGUGUCCUAAAUAUCACUGAAAUAAAAAGUAGGAAAAAGAAGCUUGAAUUUUAAGACUGAGGCUGCUCUGCAGAUUCUAGUUUGGCUUUCAGAGUUCAAGAGUGGUGGCAUCUUCACCUGAAUUCUUCAAUGCCAGGGUAAUAAACCAAAAUAGUCCUAAUCAGUAUAUGCUAGUUGAGCAUCGGCAUAAUUUUCUUUCCUCUGGCUGAUCCCAGCCCUAAAGGAAGGGUAGACCCGUGUCUUUCCAGCCCUAAAGGAAGGGUAGACCCGUGUCUUUCCAGCCCUAAAGGAAGGGCAGACCCGUGUCUUUCCAUGCCCGAGGGCCACGACGUCACUAUGCAGGGCACACGUGGCUUGGUUUAAAAAGGUCAUCUUAGAUUUAUCUUAGUAAAUGUAAUAAAUUAUUUUUUAGAUCUUGAAAUUUAUAAUAAAAAUACUUUACCUACCCUGAUCACCAAAACCUGAUGUUUUAAAUGUGCUUUCUUUUUGAAAUUUAUGUUUUCAAAUAAAAUCUCCCUAAAGCAAUAUUUAAAAAUUGGUCAAAACAAGGUCUGGGAGUAUGUUUGUGUGUCUUUCCAGCUUUAUCCUGUAGCGUGUCUUUGUUCUGUGUUUUAGUGUCCCAUUUAGGGAGUGAUGUUUUAAGGGUUUUUGUGUACUUGGAUUAAGUAAUUAGAGGUGAGUGGGGGGAAUGGGAUUAUUGAGGCAAUGAUUUUUUUCUUCAUGGGCUCUGAUAGUUGCAUUGAUUGUUCUGUAUUCUAAUUGCUAUAUUUGUGUUUGCAUAGGUGAAGAGCAAACUGGUGCGUUAUCUUGAUUUUUAAAAAGUAAUAAAUCCUAUGAGUUCCAGUAUUAACACUUGCCAGUUCUGGAUCCUCACACCCAUUGGCUGAGCGCAUUCAAGCACCAAUCGAAGCCAGGUUCAUCUCUGAGCUGCUGAAAGGAGGUGUGAGGCUUAGGAAAUUGGAGCCUGUGUUGCCCACGAAAGGAAAGAAUAAGGAAGAAAUGUGGUAUGGAAGCGGCUACUUGCUGCUUUAUUUUCCCACCUGUUAGACAUUCCUCCACAGUGAUUUGGCCAGUUGUAUUUCACGGUAAUGGAACUAGAUAGUGUUUUCCAUUGGCUUUCUCUGGUAGCUCUUGGUCAGCUCCUGAGUUAACAGGAUGUGGCAGCAUCCCUGUUCUUCCUUCACGUCCUCACCCUCUGCCUCCAGCAGUGGAAGGGAACAGCCCUCAUGAGGACUGCUUCCUACUGCAGCUCCUGCUUUUUGCUCAUACAUUUAAAAAACUAUUUCUCAAGCUUCCCCUCCUUUUGGGGGGAGGAGCUGAUAGUAGGAGGCCAUUCCUUCCACCUCCAACUUAUACCCUCUAAGUCUAAGGUGAAGGAAAGAUUCAGAAUAAAUCCAACUUGUUUAUAGAAAAGUUCUUGUUAGUCCUUAGACCUCAUCUCAACUGCUCUGUUGAAGGUAAUGAUUUAUUGGGGGGAAAAAACAACGCCAAUUUAUCCUCUCUGUAUUAAAGUGAUAAUUCUGGGCCCACAGAAAUCAGUCAGUACCUGCGGUGUGCCUUAAGGGGACUCUCAUGAUCAUCAUUCCCUUCUAGAGAACAUUCUAGAUGAAGAAAUGCAACUGUUGACCUUCUGGUUCACCCAUCUCCCCCUCGAGGCAUUCUUGAUACCCCUUCUCACCUGCAUUUCUGUCCCAGGGAUACCAGAUGCAGCCACUACCUAACUAGGCUUGUCCUGGGGGAGUGAGCCGUGAACCUGGAGACAUGGCUUUGACCCACAGCUACUGUUCAUUUCCUCAGGCUUUGCGCUGAUUCCCUCAAUAAUAUGACAGUAAGGCAAGUAGUCUCCUUGCCUUUCUCCUGAAAGGUAUGAGAUGUGGACAUUUCAGUGUUUGAAUUAUUUUAAGAGAUGUUUUAUAGAAAUAAAACGUUUUGUAGCUAAGAAUUUUCCCUUUCUCUUAAUUUCUUACAUCUUUCCACACAAACUUAUCUUUCCAAGAAUUUGAGGUGGUGAUCAUACCCAUCAAGACGGCCUUGUAGGCUAUCUGAUUGCUAACAGACACGACCUAGAGCUUCUGCCCAAAUUCCCACACAAGCAUUAUCUCGUUUAACAUCUCAGCGACAUACUGGAUACCAGAAUAAUGUUUCCUCUUCUCUGGUGCACCAAAACCUGCCCUU